CUCUCUUUGUCCAACGUAGAAGAGACAAUGGAACCCCUCUACCAGGCUGGGUCCAUUCUCAUGACGGUGAAUACCCUACAGGGGAAAAAAAUGAUAGAGAGUGGCCUCCAGUCUGGAGACUUUUCCCUGUCCCAGUCAUGGCCCUCCUGCCUCCCACCACCCGCUGACUUGGAGAUCCUGCAGCAGAAGGUGGCCGGGGUGCAACGGGAACUGGAGGACUUUAAGAAAGAGGCAUUGAAGUCCAUUCAUUACCUUGAAGACGCCUUCUGCGAGAUGAAUGGAGCCCUGGUGCAACAGGAGGAGCAGGCGGCUCGCGUGAGGCAGCGGCUAAGGGAGGAGGAGGACCGUGGCAUCGUGCGCAACAAGGUUCUCACCUUCCUGUUGCCGCGCGAGAAACAGCUCCGGGAGCACUGCAAGCGGCUGGAGGACCUGCUGCUGGACAGGGGACGUGACGCCCUGCGUGCCACCAAGAAGAGCCAGGCUGACUGAACCUCGUGGGUGGCACUAGCCAAGCACCAAGUUGAAGAUUUUUUUUAACGGAAGGAGAAACCCCAAGUCCCUACCCCCUUGCUUUCCCUUCCUCAUUUCCAUUGCUUUCCUUCUGCCUAAAUAACACCUUGCUGAGAGGCAAAAAGACUUCAAUAUUUUUUUUGGUGAAAUUCCAUUUAUCCAGCAUUCUAAAGGAAGGAGGCACCCCAGUACUGAGUCAGGCCCCUGUAACUUUCACUUGAACUGUUUUCCUGUUUGUAAUGGUACUAUUGCUCAAUGUAUACCUCUUUAUUUGUAUAGUAUAUUCUUAAACUGA